GAGUUCCUGGAAGGCUGGUUUGAAGGCGGUGCCGGGGUGGGGGUGAGGCUCAGCAGAGCCCGGGGCACAGGCCGGAGGGGCUGCAGGCGCGAGGCUGGGUUACGUGAGGAAGCUGGGGGUUUCGCGGGCAGCUUUAGAGCCCCAGUCAGGGAAACCGAGGCCGGGCUUCCUGGCUGCCUCGCGAGCCUCUUCAUGGCUCUCGCCGCCGCCCUGAGGUGCCUAGAAUGGGUUCCGGCCUCCGGGGAGGUUCCCAGUAACCGCAGGAGCCACCAUUGAUUUGGCGUCUGCUGGGUGCAAAGCCCAGCGCGCUAACCCUUUACUCGCGACCUUUCGCUUCACCUUCACAGCAGCCCUGCGAGGUGAGUGUUGUUAUUGGUGCCAUUUACAGGGGUGGAAACUGA